GCAAGGUCCACCCUAAAGGAAUUGGAGUCAGGGCCCAGGAGCCACAGGCCACUGCACUGGGGCAUCCCAGGAUUUGGAAUUCAGCUGUGAGCUCAUGAGCUGAUGGAUGUUUCCAGGAGUACCCUGAAGACCACCCAGGUGGGAGUGUAAGAUAACCUUCCAGAUAAAGAGUUGCUGCUACCAAAAGAGUGCUGACACCAUCACAGUAUGUUCCCUUCUCAACCCUGGACAUGGUUCAGAAACAGCUAAAGCAGACAAGAAUCUGGGGCAGCCAAUAUUGUACCACCUGCCAAAGCUUGGCACAAACAAUCUGGAAGCCAAAAAUUGCACAUACUGUGGAACAGAGCAAGUGGUUCUGGCCUCCCUGGGAUUUGGAUCCUGGUUUCCAGAGCUAAGAACACAAAGUCAUGAAGGUGAAGGAGGAGAAGGCUGGGGUAGGAAAGCUGGACCACACUAACCACAGGAGGAGAUUUCCGGAUCAGAAAGAAUGCCCUCCUAUCCACAUUGGGCUUCCAGUACCCACUUACCCUCAAAGAAAAACUGACCAGAAGGGACAUCUUUCAGGCCUGCAAAAAGUCCACUGGGGCCUGCGGCCAGACCAGCCACAGCAGGAACUGACUGGCCCAGGGAGUGGGGCAAGCAGCCAGGACAGCAGCAUGGAUCUUAUCAGCAGGACUCGGUCCCCAGCUGCUGAGCAGCUCCAGGACAUCCUGGGGGAGGAAGAUGAGGCUCCCAACCCCACCCUCUUUACAGAGAUGGAUACUCUGCAGCAUGACGGAGACCAGAUGGAGUGGAAGGAGUCAGCCAGGUGGAUAAAGUUUGAAGAAAAGGUAGAGGAAGGCGGCGAACGCUGGAGCAAGCCCCACGUGUCCACACUAUCCCUGCACAGCCUCUUCGAGCUCCGUACCUGCCUGCAGACGGGGACGGUGCUGCUGGAUUUGGACAGUGGCUCCUUACCACAGAUCAUAGAUGAUGUCAUUGAGAAGCAGAUUGAGGAUGGUCUCCUGCGGCCAGAGCUCCGGGAGAGGGUCAGUUACGUCCUCCUGAGGAGGCACCGCCACCAAACCAAGAAGCCCAUCCACCGCUCCUUAGCUGACAUUGGGAAGUCAGUCUCCACCACAAAUCGCAGUCCUGCCCGGAGCCCUGGUGCUGGCCCGAGUCUACACCACUCCACGGAAGACCUGCGGAUGCGGCAGAGUGCAAAUUACGGACGUCUGUGUCAUGCCCAGAGCAGAAGCAUGAAUGACAUUUCUCUCACCCCAAACACAGACCAGCGGAAAAACAAAUUCAUGAAGAAGAUCCCCAAGGACUCAGAAGCGUCCAACGUGCUCGUGGGCGAGGUGGACUUCCUAGACCAGCCAUUCAUCGCGUUCGUGCGCCUCAUCCAGUCGGCCAUGCUGGGAGGAGUGACCGAGGUGCCUGUCCCCACCAGAUUUCUGUUUAUACUACUGGGACCUUCUGGGAGAGCAAAAUCCUACAAUGAAAUUGGCCGUGCCAUUGCAACCCUCAUGGUAGAUGAUCUCUUCAGUGACGUGGCCUACAAAGCCCGCAAUCGGGAAGAUCUGAUCGCAGGAAUUGAUGAAUUUCUGGAUGAGGUCAUCGUCCUUCCUCCUGGAGAAUGGGACCCAAAUAUCCGGAUUGAGCCCCCCAAGAAGGUGCCCUCUGCUGACAAGAGGAAAUCUGUGUUCUCCCUAGCAGAGCUGGGCCAGAUGAAUGGCUCUGUGGGAGGAGGCGGCGGAGCUCCUGGAGGAGGCAAUGGAGGUGGUGGUGGUGGUGGCAGUGGCGGCGGGGCUGGCAGUGGCGGGGCCGGCGGAACAAGCAGCGGGGAUGAUGGAGAGAUGCCAGCCAUGCAUGAAAUCGGGGAGGAACUUAUCUGGACAGGAAGGUUCUUCGGUGGCCUGUGUCUGGAUAUCAAGAGGAAGUUGCCCUGGUUCCCAAGUGACUUCUAUGAUGGCUUCCACAUUCAGUCCAUCUCUGCCAUCCUAUUCAUCUACCUCGGCUGUAUCACCAACGCGAUCACCUUUGGUGGGCUUCUGGGGGAUGCCACCGACAAUUAUCAGGGAGUGAUGGAGAGCUUCCUGGGCACUGCCAUGGCUGGCUCCUUGUUCUGCCUCUUCUCGGGACAGCCUCUCAUCAUUCUCAGCAGCACGGGGCCCAUCCUCAUCUUUGAGAAGCUCCUCUUCGACUUCAGCAAAGGCAAUGGCCUGGACUACAUGGAGUUCCGCCUCUGGAUUGGCCUACACUCAGCUGUCCAGUGCCUUAUCCUAGUGGCCACAGAUGCCAGCUUUAUCAUCAAAUAUAUCACCCGCUUCACCGAGGAGGGCUUCUCCACCCUUAUCAGCUUCAUCUUCAUCUACGAUGCCAUCAAGAAGAUGAUCGGUGCCUUCAAGUACUACCCUAUCAAUAUGGACUUCAAGCCAAACUUCAUCACUACCUACAAGUGCGAGUGUGUCGCCCCUGACACAGUGAAUACAACCGUGUUCAAUGCUUCAGCCCCAUUGGCACCAGACACCAACGCUUCUCUGUACAACCUCCUUAACCUCACAGCGUUGGACUGGUCCCUGCUGAGCAAGAAGGAGUGUCUGAGCUACGGCGGGCGCCUGCUUGGGAAUUCCUGCAAGUUUAUCCCAGACCUGGCGCUCAUGUCCUUCAUCCUUUUCUUUGGGACAUACUCCAUGACCCUGACCCUGAAGAAGUUCAAAUUCAGCCGCUAUUUUCCUACCAAGGUCCGGGCCCUGGUGGCUGACUUUUCCAUUGUUUUCUCCAUCCUGAUGUUCUGUGGAAUCGAUGCCUGUUUUGGCCUAGAAACUCCCAAGCUGCAUGUGCCCAGUGUCAUCAAGCCAACGCGGCCUGACCGAGGCUGGUUCGUGGCCCCCUUUGGGAAGAACCCGUGGUGGGUAUACCCAGCAAGCAUCCUGCCCGCCCUGCUGGUGACCAUCCUGAUCUUCAUGGACCAGCAGAUCACUGCCGUCAUUGUCAACCGGAAGGAGAACAAACUGAAGAAGGCUGCCGGCUACCAUCUGGACCUGUUCUGGGUGGGCAUCCUCAUGGCUUUGUGCUCCUUUAUGGGGCUCCCCUGGUACGUGGCUGCCACGGUCAUCUCCAUCGCCCACAUCGACAGCCUCAAGAUGGAGACAGAGACCAGUGCCCCUGGGGAGCAGCCCCAGUUUCUGGGAGUCAGGGAACAGAGAGUAACCGGCAUCAUCGUCUUCAUCCUGACGGGAAUCUCUGUCUUCCUGGCUCCCAUCCUAAAGUGUAUCCCCCUGCCGGUGCUGUACGGAGUCUUCCUCUACAUGGGCGUGGCCUCCCUGAAUGGCAUCCAGUUCUGGGAACGCUGCAAGCUCUUCCUGAUGCCAGCCAAGCACCAGCCGGACCAUGCCUUCCUGCGGCACGUGCCGCUGCGCCGGAUCCACCUCUUCACCCUGGUGCAGAUCCUCUGCCUGGCGGUGCUCUGGAUCCUCAAAUCCACGGUGGCUGCCAUCAUCUUCCCGGUCAUGAUCCUGGGCCUCAUCAUCGUUCGAAGGCUUCUGGAUUUCAUCUUUUCCCAGCACGACCUGGCCUGGAUUGACAACAUCCUCCCAGAGAAGGAAAAAAAGGAGACAGACAAGAAGAGGAAGAGAAAAAAAGGGGCCCACGAGGACUGUGAUGAGGAGCCCCAGUUCCCUCCUCCCUCGGUUAUAAAGAUUCCCAUGGAAAGUGUCCAAUCAGAUCCCCAAAACGGUAUCCACUGCAUUGCCAGAAAAAGAUCUUCCAGUUGGAGUUACUCACUCUGAUUCUUCCUUCAGUGACACAGAACUUGACCGAAGCAUCACCUUGCACUUCAAAAUAUCCUGUCCAGCUUCACCUGCUUUCAGCUACUCACGGAACCCAGUGUUCAUGGUGCCACAGGUGAAGAUAGAGAUGGAGUCAGACUAUGACUUCACAGACAUGGAUAAAUACCGAAGAGAAACUGACAGUGAGACCACCCUCUAGGAUGAAGCAGCUUCUCCCAGAUGGGAGAUGGAGAGCCUGGCUUAGUCUUCACUGGGAGGGUCUUAACUUCUCUGUGCCUGUUUCCUUCUUUAUCAAACAGAGGGAGUCCGUCUGCCUAUAGAAAACUGGAGAUCUAUUGAUGAAAAGUAUUGCUUAGAUGCAAAGCUCUCCCCUUUGUAGUAAUUAAAAUACCUAAAGCUAAAUAUUAUAUUUUAUUUUAAAAUGCAGUUCAGCAUAGAAAUUCUAACAUUUCUUUGGAAAUAAAAAAAUGCUUGUUUCCCCAAACCAUAGCUAAGAUAAAGGGGCAAUAGUCAAUUCAUAUUUAAAACAAAUAUCAAUUUAAAAUUGUUUAAAGGUUAGAUUUAAAUAUAGAUGUUCUCAAACAAACUUGUAAUAUACUUUUAUGUCACUAGACCAUCUUUGGAAUAUUUGGCAAUUCUGCAUAUUAAGAAAUGCUGAAAAGGUCCUAUCUUUUCUCCCUGUCACAUCCAAUUUCCUAAGGGUUAUAUGAAAAGUUUGAACCAGCCGGGCACAGUGGCACACGCCUGUAAUCCUAGCACUUUGGGAGGCCGAGGCAGGUGAAUUGCCUGAGCUCAGGAGUUCGAGACCAGCCUAGGCAACACGGUGAAACCCCGUCUCUACUAAACUACAAAAAAUUAGCCGGGUGUGGUGGCAUGCACCUGUAGUCCCAGCUAUUCGGGAGGCUGAGGCAGGAGAAUCGCUUGAACCCAGGAGGCAGAAGUUGCAGUGAGCUGAGAUGGCACCACUGCACUCCAGCCUAGGCAACAGAGUGAGACUCCGUAUCCAAACAAAAAAAAAGUUUGAACCAUCUGCAUUAUGGGCCUUGCUCCAGAAGUGUGACUGGGGCUUUCCCAGAUUGAAAAGCCAGUUCCAAAACUCUGUUAAUGAAAGAACCAAUGCAUCUGAGUGGAUAAAUGUUUCUAAAAUAAAAUAGUUCUUGUUAAAGUGAAAUUUGAAACCACAUGUUAAAUCAAAAUGAUCCUUUAAAUUAGUAUCACUGGUUUUUCAUACCUGGAAUCACAUUUCAUGAUACAUUUGGGUGGGUCCUCCCUGCAAAUUUUCAAUGUUUAUUCCCAAAGUCAAACUCCCAUUCAUGUGAACAAUACAGGUUAGACAGAGGUAAGGUCACAUUUUACAUUACAACUUUGCAAUAUUAAUCAACCUAGUACUUUAAAGGAAUGAUUGAAAACUAUUUGGGAAGAUAAAAACCAGUUUCAAUGAAGCAAACCUAUUCCUCAUGAAACUUAAGAUCAGUCAUUUUAUCUUCAAUCCACAUUUAAUGAACACCAACCAUGUUGAUUUAAUGCCUACUAUGACCCUGACAGCCACAGUGCAUCUGACACUUACUUUCUCCAAAACAACUAUGAUUUAAACCUUGAGUAAAUCACUUGAACCUUGAGGUUAGAGUUACUAUAUUUGCUCAAGAUGACAAAUGCAGGUGCUUUCUUUUUUAAAGAAAAAUGACACUAGAUCAUUAACACCUUGAGUAUAGGACAGGUAAUUGCCUCUGUAAUUCCCAGCGUCUAGUGUAGUGCCUGGUCCAUAGAAAGCUCUCAAUAAGUGUUUGAUUACAUUUAAUCUCAGAGCUCCCUUCCAAGGGAUACUGCCAAGAGGUAAAGCUCCAAACCUCUACUCUUACUGAGAGCAGAAUUUCUUAGAAUUUCCAGAACCAUCUCCUAUGCUUAAGUAUAAAUUCUUGUCAGACACAGUGGCUCACACCUGUAAUCCCGCUACUUGGGAGGCAGAGGUGGGGGGAAUCAGCAGAGGUCAGGAGGUCAAGACCAGCCUGGGCAACAUAGUGAGACCCAUCUCUAAACAAAUGUUUAAAAAUUAGCUAGGCAUGCUGGCACACACCUGUAGUCCCAGCCAUUUCAGAGGCUGAUGCAGGAGGAUCGUUUAAGUCCAGGAGUUCAAGGCUGCAGUGAGCUAUAAUCAUGCCACUGCACUCCAGCCAGGGAGACAGCUGGAAUCCAUGUCUUAUAAACAAUAAUAAUUAAUUUUUAAAAAAAGUAUUUAUCAUCCACACCAAUCCUGGGGAAGCUAACAAUCCACCCUUAACACAUUUCAGUUUUAAAACCUGGCUGAUCUGGAAUAGAACUUUGUCCAAAUUAAAUUGUAGAAAUGCUAUGGAUUCAAGAGUAAACCUGCUUGAUUAAUCAAACAAGCUGGAAAACUACUGUUAAUUUCUUUGUUGUAAAUUGAUCACUGUAAUUUUACCUUACAUGUCAUUUAUAUUUUGUAUAUACAUGAACAUUUUAAUUUCCAUAGCUUUUAACAGGUUGACAUAAUACUUCUCCAUGCAGUAAGUCAGUCAUUUUUUCCACUUGUAACUGUAAUUCAAUAAAAUUUAAUCCUGUCUGGUCA